AAGUUUCCUGGUGCCUUUUCUAUUCCACCUUAUGAAACUUUUUCCCCGGCGUGGUCUCACUCGCGAUUUAAGGCAUAGGUGUCGCCGAGCCGGGAGGCUGGGAGUCGCCAGGCGUGCGGGGGAGAGGCCUGGGCCGCGCCGCGGCGGGGGGUGGAGGAAGAGGGCAGGCGAGGCGGGAAGGUGGGCUCUGGCCGCCGGGAGCCGGGGACGGAGCCGCCGCCGUUGCCCCUAGCGGGGAGCAGCCGGGAGGAGGGGGCCGCAGUCGGGAGAGGGGACCCCACCAUGCCCAAAGUCUUCCUGGUGAAGAGGAGGAGCCUGGGGGUCUCGGUCCGCAGCUGGGAUGAGCUCCCGGAUGAGAAAAGGGCAGACACCUACAUCCCAGUGGGCCUAGGCCGCCUGCUCCACGACCCCCCCGAGGACUGCCGCAGCGACGGCGGCAGCAGCAGCGGCAGCGGCAGCAGCAGCGCGGGGGAGCCUGGAGGAGCAGAGAGCAGCUCGUCCCCGCACGCCCCCGAGAGCGAAACCCCCGAGCCCGGCGACGCCGAGGGCCCCGAUGGACACCUGGCGACCAAGCAGCGCCCGGUCGCCAGAUCGAAAAUCAAGUUCACCACAGGCACGUGCAGCGACUCGGUGGUUCACAGCUGUGACCUGUGUGGCAAGGGCUUCCGUCUGCAGCGCAUGCUGAACCGUCACCUCAAGUGCCACAACCAGGUGAAAAGACACCUGUGCACCUUCUGCGGCAAGGGCUUCAACGACACCUUCGACCUGAAGAGGCACGUCCGCACACACACAGGCAUUCGUCCCUACAAAUGCAACGUCUGCAAUAAAGCCUUCACCCAGCGCUGCUCUCUGGAGUCCCACCUGAAGAAAAUCCAUGGGGUGCAGCAGCAGUAUGCCUAUAAGCAGCGGCGGGACAAGCUCUACGUCUGCGAGGAUUGCGGCUACACGGGCCCCACCCAGGAGGACCUGUACCUGCACGUGAACAGUGCCCAUCCGGGCAGCUCGUUUCUCAAAAAGACAUCUAAAAAACUGGCAGCCCUUCUGCAGGGCAAGCUGACAUCCGCACACCAGGAGAAUACCAGCCUGAGUGAGGAGGAGGAGAGGAAGUGAGGAGAAGGAAGGGGAGGACAGACGUUCACACUGCCACGUAUGUCUACGUGGAUUUUUGGUUUUCAGCUUCCCCCACCCCACUGGCUCUUCUUAAUUAGAAGUGACCAGUUCACCUCUGUGUCCUUUUGAAACAUCAGCAGUAGGGUCCAUUCCAAGAUUGUCAGUUGCCGUUAGUGACGUCAGGCCCUGUAACCUGUGUCCUGUCUGGCGCAGUUGCUCACAUUCACCAAAGUUUGUUUUCAUGAUCCUGAUGGCCAAGAACACCGUGUGGGAUUUUUUUUUCCCCCAAGGAUUUUCACACACGGAAGGAGAGGUAUUUCUUAGAGAGAUCAUCAUUUUAUGGUGCCUUGAAAUAAAAAUACUUCUACUUGAAAUGCUGUUUAAGCAAGGCAAGUGAAUUUUGUUAUUCUGAAAGAGUUUACAGAAACUAUUUUAAUAAAUGAAAUGUUCUUGUGAAGCUUUUAAAAGCAAAA